AUUUCCCCAAACGCAGGCGCUCGGUGGCGGUAGCCGCGGUUGUUGGCCGACCGAGUGCCGGUCAUAAGCCCCCCCCGGUGGGGGGCAGCUGGUGUGCGGAUCGCGGCGGGAGAGAGGCGCGGUAGGAACGGGUCCCCGGAGCCGUGAACCGCGGGUACAGGUGUCCUGUCUGCGCUCUCUGCCAAGCCGGCUUGCUUCCUGAUCUGUUGCUAGGGCCGCUGGACCCCGUUGCUAAGGACCCUUGAGAUCGUGAGCGCUUGGAGUGUACCCCUCCUUUCCUGGGGUAGAGGGUCAGUCGAGAGUAGCCUUCGUUAACCUUAAUUGAAACUGGUUCGCUUCUCCCCAUCACUGCCCCUUUACACCAUCCUCUACAUGUUAUUUAAUGAAAAACCACUUGAAAGGGUUACCAAGGAUAAGAUUUUUAAAGCUUGCUUUCACAAACAACUCAUGCUCCAGGCUUGUCAGUGGCAUGCUUCCAGUCUCUUUCAGAUACCCAAAUCCACCCAUGCCAAAGUCCUCCAGUCUGCUCUCCGUAUCCGUGGUUGGGUCAAAUCUAUAGAUGUGGAACCCGCAUAUACGGAGAGCCAACUGUAAUUUGUCGUUAAGUUUGUUACAGGAACAACUUUUUGACGUGAAGGAAGAUAGAAAUUUAGCCAUAAAAUUCCAUCCAAAACUUCCACUGAAUUGGAGUGAAAGGGAAGCAAUGCAGAAAUCAGAGGGCUCUGGAGGUACACAGUUGAAAAACAGAGCAACAGGUAACUAUGAUCAAAGGACAUCAUCAAGCACACAGUUAAAACACAGGAAUGCAGUUCAGGGAAGCAAAUCCUCAUUGUCAACCAGUUCUCCAGAGUCUGCAAGAAAACUUCAUCCUAGACCAAGUGAUAAACUGAACCCUAAAACAAUUAAUCCGUUUGGUGAACAGUCACGAGUGCCUUCUGCAUUUGCAGCUAUUUACUCUAAAGGAGGUAUUCCUUGCAGAUUGGUACAUGGUUCAGUAAAACACAGAUUACAGUGGGAAUGUCCUCCUGAAAGUCUUUCAUUUGAUCCACUUCUUAUUACUUUAGCUGAGGGUCUGAGAGAGACUAAGCAUCCAUACACUUUUGUGUCAAAGGAGGGUUUUAGAGAAUUACUUUUGGUCAAAGGUGCUCCUGAAAAAGCUAUUCCUUUGCUACCUAGACUGAUUCCUGUGCUAAAGGCAGCUCUGGUCCAUUCGGAUGAUGAAGUGUUUGAAAGAGGAUUGAAUGCUCUAGUUCAGCUAAGUGUCGUUGUUGGUCCUUCUCUAAACGACCAUCUGAAGCAUCUGCUUACAAGCCUUUCCAAGAGAUUAAUGGACAAGAAAUUCAAAGAGCCAAUCACCAGCGCAUUACAAAAGCUAGAGCAACAUGGUGGAAGUGGGAGCCUUAGCAUCAUCAAAUCUAAAAUUCCAACAUACUGCUCCAUAUGCUGUUGAAGAAGGGAGCCAACAAAAAUUGUUUUUUCUACCUGUUGACGUGUCAAGCACUAACUGUGGGUACUCAUUUAUUUUAUUCUUUUGUAAAUCACAGCCACCAUUCAUUAUUUACUAGGUUAAGAUGAAUAGACACUGAAUCAAAGUUAUUCAUCAACAAAAAAGAACAGUUACUAAUGGAAAGUUAUUAAAAUAAGUUCUAUAAGAGUACAAUUUUGAGGUUUAUUUUUUGUAUUUUUAUUAUUUGUGCGAAGAACCAUUAUUGAGUUUGCAAGAUAAGAUGUAUUUGUAUUUUCUAGUGUCUUUUUAUUUAUAACAACACUUUUUUGGCAAUCAGUUUGUAGCUGUGCCCUUAUUUUUAUAGAUAGUUUGCCAUUUCUUGGGUUUAAUGUUUAACAAGGCUAUAGAAGUUUAAAAUAGUGGACAAAUGUUUGUGAAUACACUUUUAAAAAAUUGUUUUAAAAGAGAAAAGCGGUCUUGCUUUGUUGCCCAGACUGGAGUGCAGUGGCAUAAUCAUAGCUCACCGCAAGCCUCAAAUUUUUGUGCUCAGAUGAUCCUUUUCAUCUCAGCCUCCUGAUUAGCUGGGACUAUAGGCGUGUGCCACCAUGCCCAGCUAAUUUUGAAAUUUGCUUGUAGAGAUGGGAUCUCACUCUGUUGUCCAGGCUGGUCUCAGAAUUCUGGUGAGUGAUCCUCCCACAGUGGACUUCCAAAGUGCUGGGAUUACAGGUGUGAGCCACCAUGCCUGGCCCCAUGAAUACACUACUAAUAUUAUUUGUAAAUAUGUAUUUUAUAAUGUACAAUGCUUGGAAAAUUUUCAGAGUAUUCUAGUUUAAAAAAUUUUUUCUAAUUCUGUAAAUUCUAUUACAAGUAUGUUGUUUAUUACAACUCAUUACAACUACCUAAAUUUUAGGUGUUAACUGUAUUUAAGUAAAUGUGUUAUUUUUGCAUUUCAUAGCCAGAAAAUACUGAUGUUCACUUAAAGAUAUUCAGCAAUUAAAAUGUUAAAACUUGUACAUGCAUUCAUUGAUUUUGUUGUGCUUAUGUUUAGCAAUUUUUAAGAAGCUUUUAAAAUAUAAUAUAGACAUAGUUCAGAAUUUUGAUGUAAUAGAAGCAAUUCCCUCUGGCUACAACAGCUGCCUGCCUGCUGGCCUUGCUUUUACCUGUUUUCAUUGCAUUGAGCACCAUCCAGAGCUAUCUGCCAUCUAGAAAGUACUGUAAGAUUUAAUUAAUUACAAAAUUUCUUGGAAAAGACCUGUAACAUAGACAGUAGAGUUAUAAACAUUUUAUUUUGCUUUUAUUUUUUCUUUUUGAAAUACAAAAUGUGCACAUUGAGUUUACACAAACACGUGAUGGCAAAUUUCAGUGUACAUGUAUUGUACUACUCUUAAUUUCUACACUGGUGAUAGCAGGGCAGCUUUCAACAUCCUAUCUCUACACCAGAAUAGAUACCUGAUUUAUUGUUGCAAAGACAGUUGCAAAUUUCCUCCUUCUGUAGCCUCUUGGUCUUUGUGAUAUUUCUACAAAACAGGGACGAUGUGUGUGGCUUUAGUAAUGUGGCAACUUUACAGUUUUGGCUAAGAUGAUUAAAAAUAAUCUGAAUUAUGAUGAGCUAAAUCAUACUGUAAUCUGGAUUAGUUGUUGAGCACUUAUUUUCUACUAAAUCUUGGUAGUAGUUGUCAAUGUAAUGGAACCACUGGUGCUUUCAAAGUGAAUUUUGCUUGCUAAUUUUGCUUGCUGUUUGUUCUUAGUAGACAGUGGGGUAGUCAAGGUUUCUUUCUUUGUCCCUGAAUGGCUUGUAAUAUAAAUAAACAUGCUGUAAGGAAGUCAGGGGAAAGAGGACAGAUUUGGCCUUUAAUGCUGUUAGGAUUACUUGUUAUUAAGCAUUACUAUAUACUGGAGGAUAGAUAUCCUGACCCUUUGCAUAUGUCUGUAAACAUCCUUGUUUUGUUUGAUGCCUUCUUCAACUUCCACUUAAUGAUUGAUACUAAUGAUUGAUACAAUAGAAAACAGCCUGUAAGAAAGAUUGAACAAAUCCAAAAUUAUUAUAUAGGCCUUGGCUGUAACAUAUUAUGGAAAAUUAAAUGCUUAUUAAAAUAAGUUUUAUUAGGCAUAUGCUGAUAUCUGAUAAUAAACUAAUUUUUAAAUGUUUAAUAAUUUUUAAAUGUUUAAAAAUGCCAGAUAAAACUAAUUUCUAACAGAAGGUGGGAAGGCCAUAGAAACUGGAACUAUGUGUUUUUUUAAUUGUUGUAAUCUUGUUUCCUUAAAGUAUAUAAAUGGAAUUUAAAUGGAAUUACAGCAUUCAAACAUGAAAAUUAAUUUAAUUUCUGGAAAUUAAAUGCAGAUGUCACUAUAUUAGAAAACCAUUCAAAAUCCUAGGACUGAAUACAUACAAAUGAGUAGCAAAAAACACUGAUAUUUUAAAAUCACUGAUAUGUGAAAGCCUCAAUAAUCCCAUGGCUAAGGAACCAAUAAAACUAUAUGCCAGAUUCUAUUACUUUUGAAUAUUCACAGAGUAUGAAAUGAGUUAGACCAUCCCCUGAACUCAGUGGCAUUAUGAAAAGGAUGCAAAUUUAUAACUGAAAGCUCAAAUCUUUUGGGGAUUGCUUUAUAUUAAAACAAAGCUUGUUUGCAUAAUAUGCUUCAGUGUCAAGCUGAGCAAUCUAUGCUAAAAGUGGUAGCUCCAACUUUAAGGGUGGUAGAAUAGUUCACAUUUGUCUGUUGGAUUCAGGAUCUAUUUGACAAGUUAAAUCACAUUUUCAAAGAGCUGCAUGGAGCGCAUUAUGUUUUCAUCCUGUAAGGGAGAAACACAGAGCGAUUAAAUUCAGCAUAUCUGCAAGGAAAAGUACACUAUUUUGCCCCUGAGUAUUGCCUCCUCCCAUCAACCACCUCAACCACCUAUGCCAAAAGCUCAAAUAUUAAGUGUUUGCAAAUGUAAAUGCCAUUCUAUUCUAUCCAUUUUCCACAUAGAUGACUAUGAAGGACCCAUUUUAUAUUUUGUGGAGUCUAUUGACCAGGCAUUAAACCACUUUAUUUAAAUCUUUACUUGGUAUUAAUAGAGGAUAUUUCUCAAAUCAUAAUGCCAAAAUGGAAACUACAGAGGUGCAGAGGUGUGUCAAAGCAAAUGAGAAUUUUGGCAUUCUAUGUAGAUCACAGGCCAAAUCACACAGACUUUUAUACAGGUACAAGGAAAAUUUGUGUGUAUGAGCCAGCAGUUCAUGAAGAUUGGAGGCUGGCGCAUAGGAGGCAGGGUGGUGGAUUAAGAGGUAACAUGUUUGCAGUAAUCAUCUCUCUUUCUGUCUGCUAGUUAUGGCUAAAGCUGCAUGGCCUGAAGGAGCCUUUAAAAAUGAAUGGUCUCUCAAUUACAGAGAAAGAAUUGGGGAGCAGAAACCACUGCUCAGUGGCUGUGUUCAGUUUAGCAUAUUCUUUAGAAAUGAGUUAGGGGACAGACUUUGGGCAUUAUUGGAGCACUUGUCAGUUGCAUGUGAAUAGCACUUACUGAGCUGUUUAUGGUAGUGGUAAAUGGUGGCUGAACCAAUAAUGGCUUCCACUGCUAGAAACCAAGUAACAUCACCGUCAAGCAGCUUAAUGUCACCAAAUUAAUUCUCUCAAAGACCACUGCAUGGAAAUCCAAGUUGAGAGACAAGCAGACAUCCAGAAAAGUAAGAACAACAAUUUAAAAAUAAAGAGAAAAACUAAAGAAACAACGGAUUUCUUUGUUUUCAGGAUUAUUUGAAAAAUUCUUUUUUUCUUUUUUUAGUUUUGAGGCAGAGUCUAUUUCUGUUGCCCAUCAUUCUGGAGUGCAGUGGCACAAUCAUGGCUCAACAGGGAUCAAGUGAUCUUCCUGCCUCAGCCUCCCAAGUAGCUGAGACUUCAGCCACGUGCCACCGUGCCCAGCUAACUUAAUUUUUUUUUGUAGAGAUAGAUAGGGUCUUGCUAUGUUGCCCACAUUGGACUCAAAAUCCUGGCCUUAAGUUAUCUUCCCGCCUCAGCCUCCCAUAGUGCUGGGAUUACAGUUGUGAGCUACUGUACCAGGCCUUAACAAUUUUUAACUGUGGUUCUGCCCACACAUCAAGUCAAAUAAUUCUAAGUAAGCUAACACUGGUUUCUUUGAUAACAGGCUACUACCUGGAGUUCUCUUCAGAGAAAAUUUUCCACUGUUUAUUUUUUGUGACUGAAGACCAUUAGUGAGUUCAGUCAAAGAGCCAUUUCUUGUCCACAUACACUAAAACAAUGACUUUUCUCUUAGAAAUCAGAUAGAAGCUUGGCCUGUUGUGAUGCCAUACUUGGCUAUCUAGGAAUUCUAAUGCUGUGGAGAUAUGAUAGAUAAUAUAUGAGUGAUGCUAAGUUUUGGCAAAGAGCAAUUCAAAUCUCAUGUAUGUUUUAUCCUCCAUGAAUACUCUCUAAGGAAUUUGGGAAUCAACACAGUACAUGUACAACUUUUGUAUCCCCAGGGUUUCCUCCAUAGCCUGACUCAGUGGGCACUCUAAAUGUUGAUUAUGUAAUUGGUGCUUGUUUUCAGAGUGGUAGGCUUAUGCUGCAUGUUGUAGAAGUGGUAAACUUAGGCAUAUGAUCUCUAUAUUUCGCCCAGUUCAUGGUAGCUAGCUGCUAAUACUCAGUUUAGCUGUUAUGAUAGCUGAAUUGAUAGUUAUUACACUUUCAUUACUUACUUUUUGGCAGCUUUCAAUGAACUCAUCUAUGGUAACAACCCCAUCUUUAUUUUUGUCCAUUUUCUGUUCAGGAAGAAAACAAAAAUUGUAUUUAGACUUAUCCCUUAAUACCCUCACACCUGGACCAAAUGAGCUGAAGCUGAUAAAAAGAAAACCUAGCUGCUUAUUUAUUUCACGUGGAGGAACUGUUUCAGAGCAGGAACCAGCAGUUUUUUAGAGAUAAAAAUGAUAGGGCCAAAUGCUUCUGGCUUUUCCCUUUUCAAUAUAAUGUGGUGAAGAUGUAGAGUCACUCUGUCCUAGGUAAAAUCCCACCUUCUAGAUGUGACAGAGCUUGCGCAAUUUGCUGAAACUUUCAGAGCUUGCUUUUUGUCUCAUCUGUAAAAUGAGAUUAAUGAGGAUUUAUAGGAUUCUUGUAAAAACUGAAUGAAAACAAAACUUGUGAAACAUGAGAACUGUUUAGUGUUGUAUCUUGGAUUUAGUGAAUGUUCAAUAAAUGCAGUUAUCAGCAUUGUAAAUUCAAAACCAAAGCUAUUAAAUUAAUAGGAUGCUAAA